AGCGAGUCUCACUCUGUCGCUCAGGCUGAAGUACAGUGGCGCGAUCUCGGCUCACUGCAACCUCUGCCUCCAGGGGUCAAGCAAUCCUCCCACCUCAGCCUCCCAAGUAGCUGGGAUUACGAGCAUGCACUACCACGCCCGGCUAAUUUUUGUACUUUUAGUAGAGAAACUUUUAACUAAAUGGGCAAGAAAGAAUGCAUCCAGCCAGAACCUCGAGACUAGCAAAUGCAUUUCUUAAAAGGGCAGGGAGGGAGACCAGAGUUUGCUUGAAAAUACUGCUUCCUUUCCUUAUCUAUGUAGGGAAGGGUUUAUCAUUCUACAUUUUGUGGUCAGCAAGCUGGCUUUCACGGGAGGAGGAUGCAUGGUCGAUUUGCCCUCUGGUAACUUUGGGAUCUUCCUCUAAACAACAGUGGACUCCCUUAGCCAAGGAAGAAGUGAAGGGAUAAUUGUGCUUACACCAGUUAGCUUUUCACACUUCUCUCUCUCCCGGUGCAGCACUGCCGGUAGGGGGAGCAGUGAGCUCCAAGUUUCCAGGAAUAAUUCAAAACACAAUUAUUUUAUAUUUUAAAAUAUAAAAUGUAUAUUUUAAAUAUAUAUACAUACAUUUCUAUAUAAUAUAUACAAAAGUUCAAUAUACGUAUAUUGAAUAUAUAUGUAUAUAAGUUCAAUAUAUAUGUAUGUAUAUUCAAUAUAUAUGUAUGUAUAUAUGUAUAUAUAUUCAAUAUAUAUGUGUAUAUAUUGAACUUUAGUCAUGUGGUGACACUUUAAACAGUACACAGAGCAGCUUCUGGGUCCAUGACCCUCCAAAAAUUUAAUUACUGAUUCUUUAGAAACUAGGCAACUCAGCCAGGUGUGGGGGCUCACGCCUGUAAUCCCAGCACUUUGGGUGGCCGAGGUGGGUGGAUCACCUGAGGUCGGGAGUUCAAGACCAGCCUGACCAGCAUGGAGAAACCCUGUCUCCACUAAAAAUACAAAAUUAGCCAGGCGUGGUGGCACAUGCCUGUAAUCCCAGCUACUUGGGAGGCUGAGGCAGGAGAAUCACUUGAACCCGGGCGAUCGCACCAUUGCACUCCAGACUGGGCAACAAGAGCAUAAGAGCAAAACUCCGUCUCAAAAAAAAAAAAAAAAAAAAACCAACCAGGCAACUCAUUUUGAUGAACUCUUAGCUAUGUGGUAGUUGCUUUUUUCAUGUGUCAAGUCUGCUAUAUUCCUGCACUCAGUAUGCAAAGAUGCAUAAAAGGCAGUCUUAGCCUUUUAGGUCAGCGGUUGGCAAACUUUCUGUGAAGGGUCAGGUGGUAAAUAUUUGAGGGUUUGCAGUUACCCGUUCUCCGUGGGAACUGCUCAACAACUCACUGCAGAGAAAGCAGCCGUGGGCAAAACGUACAGGAACGGGCGAGGCUGUGUUCCAAUAAAACUUUAUUAUUUAUGGACACUGAAAUUAGAUUUUAAUAUGAUUUUCAUGUGUCACGAAAUCUUUUUUUUUCCUAAGCAUUUAACAAAUGUAAAAACCACUCCUAGCUUGGGAGCUAUUGGAAAACAGGCAUCUGGAACCACAGUCUGCAGACCCCUGUGUGUACUCACUGUCAGUGCGGUGGGAACAAAAAGGCAGCAACGGCUGGGUCAGCCCAGGAAAGAAGACAUUUCCCAGUGGAGAGAAUGUCUGAGUGGAUAUUGAACUUUCCAGGCCACAAAGAGGAACAAGAGCAUUCAACACUGAGGAGCCUGCCUCUGCAAAGGCAGGACCCACAUGCUGGAUGUGGAGCUGGAUGGUUCCACGUGGCAAGGUUUGGGAGGCUUCUGAGAACCUGGCCUAAUGAUUCCUGUUUCCUCCCUUUUCAGAUUUUCUGAAUGGUCUUGCUUCUUUGUCUAUCUUGUCUGAUUUUCUCCUGUCUGACCUUUUCCUGGUUAAAAAUCUGGGGGAAAAUGACGGACUCCAAGCCGAUCACCAAGAGUAAAUCAGAAGCAAACCUCAUCCCGAGCCAGGAGCCCUUUCCAGCCUCUGAUAACUCAGGGGAGACACCGCAGAGAAAUGGGGAGGGCCACACUCUGCCCAAGACACCCAGCCAGGCCGAGCCAGCCUCCCACAAAGGCCCCAAAGAUGCCGGUCGGCGGAGAAACUCCCUACCACCCUCCCACCAGAAGCCCCCAAGAAACCCCCUUUCUUCCAGUGACGCAGCACCCUCCCCAGAGCUUCAAGCCAACGGGACUGGGACACAAGGUCUGGAGGCCACAGAUACCAAUGGCCUGUCCUCCUCAGCCAGGCCCCAGGGCCAGCAAGCUGGCUCCCCCUCCAAAGAAGACAAGAAGCAGGCAAACAUCAAGAGGCAGCUGAUGACCAACUUCAUCCUGGGCUCUUUUGAUGACUACUCCUCCGACGAGGACUCUGUUGCUGGCUCAUCUCGUGAGUCUACCCGGAAGGGCAGCCGGGCCAGCUUGGGGGCCCUGUCCCUGGAGGCUUAUCUGACCACAGGUGAAGCUGAGACCCGCGUCCCCACUAUGAGGCCGAGCAUGUCGGGACUCCACCUGGUGAAGAGGGGACGGGAACACAAGAAGCUGGACCUGCACAGAGACUUUACCGUGGCUUCUCCCGCUGAGUUUGUCACACGCUUUGGGGGGGAUCGGGUCAUCGAGAAGGUGCUUAUUGCCAACAACGGGAUUGCCGCCGUGAAGUGCAUGCGCUCCAUCCGCAGGUGGGCCUAUGAGAUGUUCCGCAACGAGCGGGCCAUCCGGUUUGUUGUGAUGGUGACCCCCGAGGACCUUAAGGCCAACGCAGAGUACAUCAAGAUGGCGGAUCAUUACGUCCCCGUCCCAGGAGGGCCCAAUAACAACAACUAUGCCAACGUGGAGCUGAUUGUGGACAUUGCCAAGAGAAUCCCCGUGCAGGCGGUGUGGGCUGGCUGGGGCCAUGCUUCAGAAAACCCUAAACUUCCGGAGCUGCUGUGCAAGAAUGGAGUUGCUUUCUUAGGCCCUCCCAGUGAGGCCAUGUGGGCCUUAGGAGAUAAGAUCGCCUCCACCGUUGUCGCCCAGACGCUACAGGUCCCAACCCUGCCCUGGAGUGGAAGCGGCCUGACAGUGGAGUGGACAGAAGAUGAUCUGCAGCAGGGAAAAAGAAUCAGUGUCCCAGAAGAUGUUUAUGACAAGGGUUGCGUGAAAGACGUAGAUGAGGGCUUGGAGGCAGCAGAAAGAAUUGGUUUUCCAUUGAUGAUCAAAGCUUCUGAAGGUGGCGGAGGGAAGGGAAUCCGGAAGGCUGAGAGUGCGGAGGACUUCCCGAUCCUUUUCAGACAAGUACAGAGUGAGAUCCCAGGCUCGCCCAUCUUUCUCAUGAAGCUGGCCCAGCACGCCCGUCACCUGGAAGUUCAGAUCCUCGCUGACCAGUAUGGGAAUGCUGUGUCUCUGUUUGGUCGCGACUGCUCCAUCCAGCGGCGGCAUCAGAAGAUCGUUGAGGAAGCACCGGCCACCAUCGCCCCGCUGGCCAUAUUCGAGUUCAUGGAGCAGUGUGCCAUCCGCCUGGCCAAGACCGUGGGCUAUGUGAGUGCAGGGACAGUGGAAUACCUCUAUAGUCAGGAUGGCAGCUUCCACUUCUUGGAGCUGAAUCCUCGCUUGCAGGUGGAACAUCCCUGCACAGAAAUGAUUGCUGAUGUUAAUCUGCCGGCCGCCCAGCUACAGAUCGCCAUGGGCGUGCCACUGCACCGGCUGAAGGAUAUCCGGCUUCUGUAUGGAGAGUCACCAUGGGGAGUGACUCCCAUUUCUUUUGAAACCCCCUCAAACCCUCCCCUCGCCCGAGGCCACGUCAUUGCCGCCAGAAUCACCAGCGAAAACCCAGACGAGGGUUUUAAGCCGAGCUCCGGGACUGUCCAGGAACUGAAUUUCCGGAGCAGCAAGAACGUGUGGGGUUACUUCAGCGUGGCCGCUACUGGAGGCCUGCACGAGUUUGCGGAUUCCCAAUUUGGGCACUGCUUCUCCUGGGGAGAGAACCGGGAAGAGGCCAUUUCGAACAUGGUGGUGGCUUUGAAGGAACUGUCCAUCCGAGGCGACUUUAGGACUACCGUGGAAUACCUCAUUAACCUCCUGGAGACCGAGAGCUUCCAGAACAACGACAUCGACACCGGGUGGUUGGACUACCUCAUUGCUGAGAAAGUGCAGGCGGAGAAACCGGAUAUCAUGCUUGGGGUGGUAUGCGGGGCCUUGAACGUGGCCGAUGCGAUGUUCAGAACGUGCAUGACAGAUUUCUUACACUCCCUGGAAAGGGGCCAGGUCCUCCCAGCGGAUUCACUACUGAACCUCGUAGAUGUGGAAUUAAUUUACGGAGGUGUUAAGUACAUUCUCAAGGUGGCCCGGCAGUCUCUGACCAUGUUCGUUCUCAUCAUGAAUGGCUGCCACAUCGAGAUUGAUGCCCACCGGCUGAAUGAUGGGGGGCUCCUGCUCUCCUACAAUGGGAACAGCUACACCACCUACAUGAAGGAAGAGGUUGACAGUUACCGAAUUACCAUCGGCAAUAAGACGUGUGUGUUUGAGAAGGAGAACGAUCCUACAGUCCUGAGAUCCCCCUCGGCUGGGAAGCUGACACAGUACACAGUGGAGGAUGGGGGCCACGUUGAGGCUGGGAGCAGCUACGCUGAGAUGGAGGUGAUGAAGAUGAUCAUGACCCUGAACGUUCAGGAAAGAGGCCGGGUGAAGUACAUCAAGCGUCCAGGUGCCGUGCUGGAAGCAGGCUGCGUGGUGGCCAGGCUGGAGCUCGAUGACCCUUCUAAAGUCCACCCGGCUGAACCGUUCACAGGAGAACUCCCUGCCCAGCAGACACUGCCCAUCCUCGGAGAGAAACUGCACCAGGUCUUCCACAGCGUCCUGGAAAACCUCACCAACGUCAUGAGUGGCUUUUGUCUGCCAGAGCCCGUUUUUAGCAUAAAGAUAGCCACCAUCCUGGACUGCCAUGCAGCCACCCUGCAGCGGAAGGCUGAUCGAGAGGUCUUCUUCAUCAACACCCAGAGCAUCGUGCAGUUGGUCCAGAGAUACCGCAGCGGGAUCCGCGGCUAUAUGAAAACAGUGGUGUUGGAUCUCCUGAGAAGAUACUUGCGUGUUGAGCACCAUUUUCAGCAAGCCCACUACGACAAGUGUGUGAUAAACCUCAGGGAGCAGUUCAAGCCAGACAUGUCCCAGGUGCUGGACUGCAUCUUCUCCCACGCACAGGUGGCCAAGAAGAACCAGCUGGUGAUCAUGUUGAUCGAUGAGCUGUGUGGCCCAGACCCUUCCCUGUCGGACGAGCUGAUCUCCAUCCUCAACGAGCUCACUCAGCUGAGCAAAAGCGAGCACUGCAAAGUGGCCCUCAGAGCCCGGCAGAUCCUGAUUGCCUCCCACCUCCCCUCCUACGAGCUGCGGCAUAACCAGGUGGAGUCCAUUUUCCUGUCUGCCAUUGACAUGUACGGCCACCAGUUCUGCCCCGAGAACCUCAAGAAAUUAAUACUUUCGGAAACAACCAUCUUCGACGUCCUGCCUACUUUCUUCUAUCACGCAAACAAAGUCGUGUGCAUGGCGUCCUUGGAGGUUUACGUGCGGAGGGGCUACAUCGCCUAUGAGUUAAACAGCCUGCAGCACCGGCAGCUCCCGGACGGCACCUGCGUGGUAGAAUUCCAGUUCAUGCUGCCGUCCUCCCACCCAAACCGGAUGACCGUGCCCAUCAGCAUCACCAACCCUGACCUGCUGAGGCACAGCACAGAGCUCUUCAUGGACAGCGGCUUCUCCCCACUGUGCCAGCGCAUGGGAGCCAUGGUAGCCUUCAGGAGAUUCGAGGACUUCACCAGAAAUUUUGAUGAAGUCAUCUCUUGCUUCGCCAACGUGCCCAAAGACACCCCCCUCUUCAGCGAGGCCCGCACCUCCCUAUACUCCGAGGAUGACUGCAAGAGCCUCAGAGAAGAGCCCAUCCACAUUCUGAAUGUGUCCAUCCAGUGUGCAGACCACCUGGAGGAUGAGGCACUGGUGCCGAUUUUACGGACAUUCGUACAGUCCAAGAAAAAUAUCCUUGUGGAUUAUGGACUCCGACGAAUCACAUUCUUGAUUGCCCAAGAGAAAGAAUUUCCCAAGUUUUUCACAUUCAGAGCAAGAGAUGAGUUUGCAGAAGAUCGCAUUUACCGUCACUUGGAACCUGCCCUGGCCUUCCAGCUGGAACUUAACCGGAUGCGUAACUUCGAUCUGACCGCCGUGCCCUGUGCCAACCACAAGAUGCACCUUUACCUGGGUGCUGCCAAGGUGAAGGAAGGUGUGGAAGUGACGGACCAUAGGUUCUUCAUCCGCGCCAUCAUCAGGCACUCUGACCUGAUCACAAAGGAAGCCUCCUUCGAAUACCUGCAGAACGAGGGUGAGCGGCUGCUCCUGGAGGCCAUGGACGAGCUGGAGGUGGCGUUCAAUAACACCAGCGUGCGCACCGACUGCAACCACAUCUUCCUCAACUUCGUGCCCACUGUCAUCAUGGACCCCUUCAAGAUCGAGGAGUCCGUGCGCUACAUGGUUAUGCGCUACGGCAGCCGGCUGUGGAAACUCCGUGUGCUACAGGCUGAGGUCAAGAUCAACAUCCGCCAGACCACCACCGGCAGUGCCGUUCCCAUCCGCCUGUUCAUCACCAAUGAGUCGGGCUACUACCUGGACAUCAGCCUCUACAAAGAAGUGACUGACUCCAGAUCUGGAAAUAUCAUGUUUCACUCCUUCGGCAACAAGCAAGGGCCCCAGCACGGGAUGCUGAUCAAUACUCCCUACGUCACCAAGGAUCUGCUCCAGGCCAAGCGAUUCCAGGCCCAGACCCUGGGAACCACCUACAUCUAUGACUUCCCGGAAAUGUUCAGGCAGGCUCUCUUUAAACUGUGGGGCUCCCCAGACAAGUAUCCCAAAGACAUCCUGACAUACACUGAAUUAGUGUUGGACUCUCAGGGCCAGCUGGUGGAGAUGAACCGACUUCCUGGUGGAAAUGAGGUGGGCAUGGUGGCCUUCAAAAUGAGGUUUAAGACCCAGGAGUACCCGGAAGGACGGGAUGUGAUCGUCAUCGGCAAUGACAUCACCUUUCGCAUUGGAUCCUUUGGCCCUGGAGAGGACCUUCUGUACCUGCGGGCAUCCGAGAUGGCCCGGGCAGAGGGCAUUCCCAAAAUUUACGUGGCAGCCAACAGUGGCGCCCGUAUUGGCAUGGCAGAGGAGAUCAAACACAUGUUCCACGUGGCUUGGGUGGACCCAGAAGACCCCCACAAAGGAUUUAAAUACCUGUACCUGACUCCCCAAGACUACACCAGAAUCAGCUCCCUGAACUCCGUCCACUGUAAACACAUCGAGGAAGGAGGAGAGUCCAGAUACAUGAUCACGGAUAUCAUCGGGAAGGAUGAUGGCUUGGGCGUGGAGAAUCUGAGGGGCUCAGGCAUGAUUGCUGGGGAGUCCUCUCUGGCUUACGAAGAGAUCGUCACCAUUAGCUUGGUGACCUGCCGAGCCAUUGGGAUUGGGGCCUACUUGGUGAGGCUGGGCCAGCGAGUGAUCCAGGUGGAGAAUUCCCACAUCAUCCUCACAGGAGCAAGUGCUCUCAACAAGGUCCUGGGAAGAGAGGUCUACACAUCCAACAACCAGCUGGGUGGCGUUCAGAUCAUGCAUUACAAUGGUGUCUCCCACAUCACCGUGCCAGAUGACUUUGAGGGGGUUUAUACCAUCCUGGAGUGGCUGUCCUAUAUGCCAAAGGAUAAUCACAGCCCUGUCCCUAUCAUCACACCCACUGACCCCAUUGACAGAGAAAUUGAAUUCCUCCCAUCCAGAGCUCCCUACGACCCCCGGUGGAUGCUUGCAGGAAGGCCUCACCCAACUCUGAAGGGAACGUGGCAGAGCGGAUUCUUUGACCACGGCAGUUUCAAGGAAAUCAUGGCACCCUGGGCGCAGACCGUGGUGACAGGACGAGCAAGGCUUGGGGGGAUUCCCGUGGGAGUGAUUGCUGUGGAGACACGGACUGUGGAGGUGGCAGUCCCUGCAGACCCUGCCAACCUGGAUUCUGAGGCCAAGAUAAUUCAGCAGGCAGGACAGGUGUGGUUCCCAGACUCAGCCUACAAAACCGCCCAGGCCGUCAAGGACUUCAACCGGGAGAAGUUGCCCCUGAUGAUCUUUGCCAACUGGAGGGGGUUCUCCGGUGGCAUGAAAGACAUGUAUGACCAGGUGCUGAAGUUUGGAGCCUACAUCGUGGACGGCCUUAGACAAUACAAACAGCCCAUCCUGAUCUAUAUCCCGCCCUAUGCGGAGCUCCGGGGAGGCUCCUGGGUGGUCAUAGAUGCCACCAUCAACCCGCUGUGCAUAGAAAUGUAUGCAGACAAAGAGAGCAGGGGUGGUGUUCUGGAACCAGAGGGGACAGUGGAGAUUAAGUUCCGAAAGAAAGAUCUGAUAAAGUCCAUGAGAAGGAUCGAUCCAGCUUACAAGAAGCUCAUGGAACAGCUAGGGGAACCUGAUCUCUCCGACAAGGACCGAAAGGACCUGGAGGGCCGGCUAAAGGCUCGCGAGGACCUGCUGCUCCCCAUCUACCACCAGGUGGCGGUGCAGUUCGCCGACUUCCAUGACACACCCGGCCGGAUGCUGGAGAAGGGCGUCAUAUCUGACAUCCUGGAGUGGAAGACCGCACGCACCUUCCUGUAUUGGCGUCUGCGCCGCCUCCUCCUGGAGGACCAGGUCAAGCAGGAGAUCCUGCAGGCCAGCGGGGAGCUGAGUCACGUGCAUAUCCAGUCCAUGCUGCGUCGCUGGUUCGUGGAGACGGAGGGGGCUGUCAAGGCCUACUUGUGGGACAACAACCAGGUGGUUGUGCAGUGGCUGGAACAGCACUGGCAGGCAGGGGAUGGCCCGCGCUCCACCAUCCGUGAGAACAUCACGUACCUGAAGCACGACUCUGUCCUCAAGACCAUCCGAGGCCUGGUUGAAGAAAACCCCGAGGUGGCCGUGGACUGUGUGAUAUACCUGAGCCAGCACAUCAGCCCAGCUGAGCGGGCGCAGGUCGUUCACCUGCUGUCUACCAUGGACAGCCCGGCCUCCACCUGACCGUGGCCCGCCCAGCCACUCCCGGGACCACGGCAAAAGGAACCACCCAGACCCACCACCCGUACACCCUCAGCAGACCCUGAAGACUUGCUUUUAAACAAAGAAAAUCCUGGGCACUUCUGCAGGGCUGCUGGUUCCGAGCUGACACCCGUCUUAACAAAAGGCCCAGGAGUGCCUCUUCCAAACAAAAACAGCCUCCUCUCCAUAGCUGGGAAGUUUAUUUUGUUUUGUCUCUGAAGACAGCAGUUUUAUUGCAUCACUAAAUCUAAUCAAGCUAAAACAUCCCUGUUUCCUUUUGCAAAACAGUGCCUGGCAUGUGGGAUCCAGGCGUUCUUUAGGAUCCUUGGAUACCACAUCGUGAAAUCUUUUAUUUUUUUACUCUGAGACCAGCACCAGAUGUAAGUAAGCAUCUCAUAUAUUUCAGCCAAAUAAAUGGGCCAAGGGAAAAAAAUAUAUAUAUAUAGACAGGACUAGAGAAAACCUAUUUUUGUAAUGAUGUUUCUUUGGAUACUGUCUAGUCACCCAGAAAAAUGUAUGGAUGAAUUUUUUUUUUUUUUUUUGAGACAAAGUCUCACUGUGUCAUGCAGGCUGGAGUGCAGUGGCAUGAUCUCACUGCAACCUCCAUCUCCUGUCUCAGCCUCCUAGAUAACUGGGAUUACAGGUGCCCACCACCAUGCCCGGCUAAUUUUUGUAUUUUUGGUAGAGACAGAGUUUCACCAGGUUGGUCAGGCUGGUCUCAAACUCUUGACUUCAGGUAAUCCACCCACCUUGGCCUCCCAAAGUGCUGGGAUUACAGGCAUGAGCCACCAUCUUCAGCCAGAUGAUUUUUUUAUUGAGAGAGUGAAAUGCUAUUUUGUUCCCCAAAUGGCGCUAGUGAAUCACUAGGAGGGUCCCACUGAUAGGCCAUGUUUAGCACUGGUUGCCAGGGAUUCUCUUUUUGAGAGAGGGAAAGCAAAAUGAAUGGAAGUACCCAGCUGGAGGUUUCAGGGCUUCUGGAGGAUGCUCUCGCAUAGCUCGAGGUCCUCUGCCCACCUCUUCUCUCCAAGGAAAAUGAGGACUGCCCCUUCCCCCUGCAGGAUUGGCCCCCAGCCUGCGCAUGCACCCUCCUCUUGCCCAAGUGGGGAGCACAGAGGCGGAGAGGAAUCCCUUACCACACCCACGGCCCAGCUUGCUCACGAGUGUCACCUCUGUGACGGUCACCACUGCUCCCUUGGAGGGCCACUUGAGUUACUGUUGCUUCCUCGCCUGCUGGCUUGAUGAGCACCGAUGGUGGGAUCUGACCCCGAGGGGCAGAGCUGUCGGUGACUGAGGACUGGACUGUGGUGACCAUGCCGAUUUGCUCAGGGAGAACGUUGCAAUGCACCCAGCAGCUCCUGGCUCUGCAGGCGGCACAGCCUGGGGCCCUGUGAUCCUCUGGUUUCUUCCAUUGGGGCGGAGUCGGGGAUGGAGGGAGCUGGCCACAACCCACUGCUCUGAUGGGUGGUUUGUCCAAGGAUGCUGAAUGUAAUGCCUGGUCAAUGUGGAAGCCCAUGAGGUUGCCCAGGGAAGCCUCCAAAAGCUGGGAUGCUUGAGGGUAUCCAAGUUGAAAAAGACAAAAUCUGACCAUCAGCCAGUGACAGUCCUGGCAAAUGAAGGUGGGGCGGGGCAGUGAGGGGUGGGAGAAGGUGAAUGAUUCAUUAUUCCACCCCGAGGUUUGCUGGGGUGAGGGGAAGAAUCGAUGCUGCUUUGGGAACUGAAGGUUUUUCUGUUGGGAAGGCCCUCUUGGUUUUGGAGAGAAAGACAAGUUAUGAGUAGCUGCUACCCUGGAACGGUGGGCAGAGAGCCUACUAGGAAAUGUGCAGAAUAAACUAUUUUUUGAAGGAAA